UGCUGCUCUCGGUUUAGUCCAAGAUCAGCGAUAUCACGCGUCCCCCGGAGCAUCGCGUGCAGGAGCCAUGGCGCGGGAGCUAUACCACGAAGAGUUCGCCCGGGCGGGCAAGCAGGCGGGGCUGCAGGUCUGGAGGAUUGAGAAGCUGGAGCUGGUGCCCGUGCCCCAGAGCGCUCACGGCGACUUCUACGUCGGGGAUGCCUACCUGGUGCUGCACACGGCCAAGACGAGCCGAGGCUUCACCUACCACCUGCACUUCUGGCUCGGAAAGGAGUGUUCCCAGGAUGAAAGCACAGCUGCUGCCAUCUUCACUGUUCAGAUGGAUGACUAUUUGGGUGGCAAGCCAGUGCAGAAUAGAGAACUUCAAGGAUAUGAGUCUAAUGACUUUGUUAGCUAUUUCAAAGGCGGUCUGAAAUACAAGGCUGGAGGCGUGGCAUCUGGAUUAAAUCAUGUUCUUACGAACGACCUGACAGCCAAGAGGCUCCUACAUGUGAAGGGUCGUAGAGUGGUGAGAGCCACAGAAGUUCCCCUUAGCUGGGACAGUUUCAACAAGGGUGACUGCUUCAUCAUUGACCUUGGCACCGAAAUUUAUCAGUGGUGUGGUUCCUCGUGCAACAAAUAUGAACGUCUGAAGGCAAACCAGGUAGCUACUGGCAUUCGGUACAAUGAAAGGAAAGGAAGGUCUGAACUAAUUGUCGUGGAAGAAGGAAGUGAACCCUCAGAACUUAUAAAGGUCUUAGGGGAAAAGCCAGAGCUUCCAGAUGGAGGUGAUGAUGAUGACAUUAUAGCAGACAUAAGUAACAGGAAAAUGGCUAAACUAUACAUGGUUUCAGAUGCAAGUGGCUCCAUGAGAGUGACUGUGGUGGCAGAAGAAAACCCCUUCUCAAUGGCAAUGCUGCUGUCUGAAGAAUGCUUUAUUUUGGACCACGGGGCUGCCAAACAAAUUUUCGUAUGGAAAGGUAAAGAUGCUAAUCCCCAAGAGAGGAAGGCUGCAAUGAAGACAGCUGAAGAAUUUCUACAGCAAAUGAAUUAUUCCAAGAAUACCCAAAUUCAAGUUCUUCCAGAAGGAGGUGAAACACCAAUCUUCAAACAGUUUUUUAAGGACUGGAGAGAUAAAGAUCAGAGUGAUGGCUUCGGGAAAGUUUAUGUCACAGAGAAAGUGGCUCAAAUAAAACAAAUUCCCUUUGAUGCCUCAAAAUUACACAGUUCUCCGCAGAUGGCAGCCCAGCACAAUAUGGUGGAUGAUGGUUCUGGCAAAGUGGAGAUUUGGCGUGUAGAAAACAAUGGUAGGAUCCAAGUUGACCAAAACUCAUAUGGUGAAUUCUAUGGUGGUGACUGCUACAUCAUACUCUACACCUAUCCCAGAGGACAGAUUAUCUACACGUGGCAAGGAGCAAAUGCCACACGAGAUGAGCUGACAACAUCUGCGUUCCUGACUGUUCAGUUGGAUCGGUCCCUUGGAGGACAGGCUGUGCAGAUCCGAGUCUCCCAAGGCAAAGAGCCUGUUCACCUACUGAGUUUGUUCAAAGACAAACCGCUCAUUAUUUACAAGAAUGGAACAUCAAAGAAAGGAGGUCAGGCACCUGCUCCCCCUACACGCCUCUUUCAAGUCCGGAGAAACCUGGCAUCUAUCACCAGAAUUGUGGAGGUUGAUGUUGAUGCAAAUUCACUGAAUUCUAACGAUGUUUUUGUCCUGAAACUGCCACAAAAUAGUGGCUACAUCUGGGUAGGAAAAGGUGCUAGCCAGGAGGAGGAGAAAGGAGCAGAGUAUGUAGCAAGUGUCCUAAAGUGCAAAACCUUAAGGAUCCAAGAAGGCGAGGAGCCAGAGGAGUUCUGGAAUUCCCUUGGAGGGAAAAAAGACUACCAGACCUCACCACUACUGGAAACCCAGGCUGAAGACCAUCCACCUCGGCUUUACGGCUGCUCUAACAAAACUGGAAGAUUUGUUAUUGAAGAGAUUCCAGGAGAGUUCACCCAGGAUGAUUUAGCUGAAGAUGAUGUCAUGUUACUAGAUGCUUGGGAACAGAUAUUUAUUUGGAUUGGCAAAGAUGCUAAUGAAGUUGAGAAAAAAGAAUCUCUGAAGUCUGCCAAAAUGUACCUUGAGACAGACCCUUCUGGAAGAGACAAGAGGACACCAAUUGUCAUCAUAAAACAGGGCCAUGAGCCACCCACAUUCACAGGCUGGUUCCUGGGCUGGGAUUCCAGCAAGUGGUAAAUUGGUAUUUGUAAAAAGCAAACAAACAUUACAAGGCAGUUAUCUCAUUGCUGUUUUGGGAGAGGAACGGGAAAAGCUUUUUGCUUAUUUGUCUUUUGAAAAUUAAGGCUGGGCGCGGUGGCUCACACCUGUAAUCCCAGCACUUUGAGAGGAUGAGGUAGGCGGAUCACUGGGGUCAGGAUUUCGAGACCAGCCUGGCCAACAUGGCGAAACCUCGCCUCUACUAAAAAUACAAAAAAAUUAGCUGCGCGUGGUGGUGCACGCCUGUAGUCCCUGCUACUUGGAAGGCUGAGACAGGAAAAUUGCUUGAACCCAGGAGGCUGAGGUUGCAGUGAGCCAGGAUUGCGCCACCACACUCCAGCCUGGGCAACAGAGACUCUGUCUCAAAAAAAAAAAAAAAAAAAAUUAACCUCAACCAAACGCCUAUUUUUUAAUGCUUAGUUUUGGCUUGAAAUUCUUCUUCACCUGGAGUUUUCUUACGUUAAUACAUUAAAAUAACCUGAAGGAAACUUUCGUUAUGGGCCAAUAUUAGCUCUUAUGGAAACUGAUUUAUAUCUUUUUUAUGACCUUUCAAAAGUAAAAUACUAUGCAUAAUCUAGAAAGAUUUGUCAGAUAGGAAAUUUUAUAAUGCAUUAGCCAUUAGUCAGAGUUGUUUUUUAACAUGCCAGAGAAAAAGUUGUAAUGCCUUGGAAGUUAUUCUCUUUUCUAUAGAUUGUGUUCAAAAGAUGUGUAUACUUGCAAUAAGGUUUAUGUUAAGGUGGCUUUAACAAUUGGUUGCUAUUUUCCUUCUUUAGUCAAUAUGACUUUGAUGUCAUUAACUGCUAAGUGUUAUUUUCUAAGAGGAAUUUUAUCUUUUUUUUAACCUUAUUAAAAGCCUUUGAAAACACAGCUCUUUCAUGACAAAAUGAAUUGUAUUGUUAUCCACUUAGAUACAUGUACAUGUACAGUACAUGUUUAAUAUCACAGGAGAUCAAAAAGACAAUGCACAGGGGAGUAUCCCAGGGAGCAGAGCCAAGUUCAAGUAAGUUAACGAUAUCAAGUUACUUACUGGCAGGUAGCCACUAGAGAAUCUUAGCAAUUUUUGUCCUGCAAGAUUUCAGCAAAGCUACAGAAAAGUGAGUUUUUAUGUUUUCCAUUCUUCCCUUUUCUAAGUAAUAAUUUUUAUCGCAGUUACCCUGAUUCUAUUCCAUUCCAUUCUAUUCUAUUCUAUUAUUUCAUUCUAUUUUAUUUCCAAUAUACCAUUGUAUAUCAGUAUAUACUGAUACACUGAGUGGCAGUUGCAUUAUCUACUAAUCUAUAUAGGUCAUUGAAAAAGAAGAAGCUACGUUAGAACCCAUGGAAAGAACUUUGCCUCAUGUAGAGAUUCUAGAUUCUUAGCCAAAAGCUCAGAAUUGUUGGGCCCUAAAGGAUGAACAAUGUAGGGUCCAACAAUUCAUCCCACAUGAAUUUUUCUCAUCCUUCAUGUGGAAUGAAAAAACUAAAGAGACAACUGACUUACCACACAAAUGGACUAUGGUAGAAGCUGCUGUCCCUUAGUAUUGAAUAUCUCUAUUUUCUUUUAAUCAUAGAAUUCACUGAUAUUUUAGCAGAUAAUGUGGCCGUCCAGGCAGGCAUGAGAUUUCUCAGCCUUACUUCAACUUGAUUAUGACCAUGUGACCCAAUUCUGACAUUUGCCUAAAGGAAAAUUUACCUAAAAAGGCGUUUUCUUGCUAUGGCAGUGUAACCUGUACUAAUAAAUAUAGUGCUAGUCCUGCAUGCAACAAAAAUGAUGUAAGUAGACAUUUAACAUUUCUAGGAAUGUAAUUGAGUGAAAAAUAAUUUUUAAAAAUAUUUAUAAAUAUCUUCUGGGUCAAGCUGAAUAUUUUUUGAAGGAUGAUGAGAAUAAAAUGAUUUAAUAAGUAGUACUUUUUCACAAAAUUAGUAAAGGUCAAGGUGAGUGGCUUAGGGUACACUGUAUUUUACGAUGUUUCUCUAGUUUAGCCAGUGGUUUUUCUCAUCUCCAAUUUAUAGCACAGGCCGAGGCAUAUAGUAGGGUCUCAGUUAAUAUUUAUUGAAUGGCAAUAUCAAAAAUGAGAUCAGCAGCAAGAUGAUAAGGCAGAAUAAAAGUUGCUGAGAGCCUAAAAUGAUUAUUCAGUUCUGUUGCAGGGUUUUAACCUGCCCAAAGGAUGGAAAAAGAAGAACAUAAGCAUAAUUUCUGAAUGCAUCACGGCAAAGAUGCAUGUACUCAUGAAGCAUAAAAUUAAAAAUAUGAUACAUUCACUACAUGAAAAUAUGAUAUACGGUUUUUCUUCAGUAUCCGCGGGAGAUUGGCUCGAGGAACCCCAUGGAUACCAACAUCCUUGAAUGCUCAAGUCCCUUAUAUAAAACGGCAUAGUAUUUGCAUAAAACCUAUACCAUUCUCCUGUAUACUCUAAGUCAUCUCUGCGUUACUUAUAAUACCUAAUACAGUGUAAACGCUGUGUAAACAGUUGUUAUACUAUAUUGGUUUUUUAAUUUGCAUUACUUUUGUAUUGUUGUAUUAUUUUAUUGUUUUUCCCCAAAUAGUUUUGAUCCGCAGAUGUAGAACCCACAGAUAUGAUAAAUCAACUGUAUCUAGUACCCAAAACAGAUGAGUAACUUAGAAAUUAAUAUGUAAUACAUACAGCUAAUGUUAUAGCUACUUAAGGAAUUCCUUUCACUGAAAAGAAACUCUUACAAAUCAAUGAGUCAACAACCCAAUGGAAAAAUGGCCAAAAGACAUGAAUAGAAGUUCACAGAAAAGAAUGAAAAUGACCAGUAAAUAAUGAAAAGAUGUUCUAAGACACUCUUAAUUAAAUAAAUUCACAAUAAAAUAAUCAUACUUUUAUCUAUCUACCAGAUUAGCAAAUGUUAAAAUAUUAAAAUGUUAGUGGUCAUCAAAAUGUAGGGUUACAGGUUCACCCAUACACUGUUAAUAGAUGUAUAAACUGGUCAAAACUUUUUGAUCCAUAGCACAGUAUUACUUUUGUAAACAUACACAAAAAAUAUUAUAUAUUUGCCAAACGUAUGUACUAAUCUAAAACCAAACACAUUAGACUAGGUACAUGUGGAGAAAGAGAUACAGGUGUUCCCUAGCAAGUUAAUAUGCUUGUGUCUCUUCAAACCAAUAUAUUGGCAUAUUUAUCUAAUAUUUAAUCAGAAGAAAGAAAGAACAGAAAGACCCAGGAAGCCUACUGUUAGUAGAGGUCAGCCUCAUCUUUUCUCUCUGAUUCAAGAAAUUCAUACUCAACUCAGUCAAACAGAGGUCCUGCAUUUACCUCUUGGUGCCGGAGAGCCUUGGUGAGCCAUUUAGAUCCUCUGUAUCUUCUCAAGCACAAUCCUCAGUGUUCUCUUCUCGUCUUAGAUAGCUCAUCAAAUAAUAUUUCCCACCACUUAUUUCUAGCAGUUCUGGUAAAGAGAAUGGCCUUCACAUUGUAUUUUGAACAAUGUUUUGGCCUCCAGUAAUGAUUAGGAACACACUAUAAACAUAAAACAUCAGUCCACUUAACUCAUUAUUCAGUCAUCAAGCAAUUCUUGUCCCAAUCAUUCUCCAAAGCUAUAUACUGUGAAUUUAUACUGUUGUGUAGUGACACAAGCCCUUCUGCUGAAAAAGUAGGUAGAUAAUUACUUUGAACUGAAAGAAAACACUUAUUUUAUUUUCUUUUAAACCUAAUUUAUUUUAAACCUAAUUUAUUUAUUUUAAACCUAAUUUAUUUUAAACCUAAUUUAUUUAUUUUAAACAUUUAUUUUAAACCUAAUUCAUUUGAACUGAACUUGAAUUUAAAAGCCUACAAAUGCCCCGCAUAUGUAGAAUUAUCAUUCAUUCCGUGUUCUUGCUCUUGGAUAAAACGGACAACUCAGAGAAAAAACUGGCUUAUAAAUGCACUUCACAAAAACUGUUAGAAAAGUAGCCAUUAAACCUGUAAAAAGGCCGGGCGCAGUGGCUGACGCCUGUAAUCCCAGCACUUUGAAAGGCCAAGGCGGUUGGAUCACGAGGCCAGGAGUCCGAGACCAGCCUGACCAACAUAGUGAAACCCCGUCUCUACUAAAAAUACAAAAAAUUAGCUGGGCGUAGUGGCGGGCGCCUGUAAUCCUAGCUACUCGGGAGGCUGAGGCAGGAGAAUCGCUUGAACCCGGGAGGCGGAGGUUGGAGCGAAAGUACGCGCCACUGUACUCCAGCCUGCGUGACGAUGAGAGUCUCCGUCUCGGGGGAAGAAAAAAAAAACCUGUAAAAAGUGGCUCAACUUUAAUAUUCAUUAGGAAAUGACUAAAAUCAAAUAUUUUACUUGGUAAUGCCAAGUAAAAAUACAGGAGAGGAUAUAGUGAAACUGGAGCUUACAUCCACUACUUGGGAAGUAUAAAUUGAUACAAUGGGUUUGAACAGUUUUUGUAUUUUCUACUAAAAUGAACAUACACAUAUCCUAUAAUCCAGAAAUCCCACUCCAUGGUGUGUACCCAACAAAAAUGCAUACAUGUGUGUACUAAAGGAUAUAAUAUGAUUUUUUUUUUUUUUUUUUUUUUUUUGAGAUAGGUUCUCACUCUGUUGCCCAGGCUGGAGUACAGUAGCGAUCUCUGCUCACUGCAAUCUCUGCCUCCUGGGUUCAAGCAAUCCUCCCACCUCAGUCUCCCCAGGAGCUGGGACUCUAGGUGCGUGCCACCACGCCCAGCUAAUUCUUUGUAGAGAUGGGGUUUUGCCAUGUUGUCCAGGCUGGUCUUGAACUCCUAGACUCAGGAAAUCCACCUGCCUUGGCCUCCCAAUAUGCUGGGAUUACAGGCAUGAGCCACCGCAUCUGGACACGAAUUUUUAAGUUUUAUAUAUGUGUGUGUAUAUAUAUAUAUAUAUAUAUAUAUAUAUAUAUAUUUUUUUUUUUUUUUUUUUUUUUUUUGCAUUGGCAAAAAAACAAAGAUAUUGUUUAGCAAUUUCCUUGUAUAAUGCAAUCAGUGGAAGACAAAUCAGAGGUAUUAUUUUCCCUUGGGCCUUUGCAGCCUGUGUUGUUUUUCUCUUUUUCAUAUUGAUGUGAAAAGCAGCCAAGUAUUAUUUGACAACAUCAGUCCCUUAUUAAGAUGUUAUUUCUAGUUUAUAAUUGACUAUGGCAUUUGCAUGCAUUUCAUCAUGUCUCCAUUUCUUCGGAAUGAUAAUUUCUAAUAUACUUUUCUUCUAUUAUAGGAAUAAGAAUUCAGUAGUCAUAUUUCCUGUUGCCUAUAAAAAAUUGAUGCUUUAAUUUAGUUAACAUGACAAACUCCAUCUUAUUUAGAGAGAUUAUUUUUGAUGUUAUUAUAAUAAAAAUGACACCUUUACUAAAAAUGUCUCAUCAUAAAUUGUUUUCCAUUAUUUCUGUGCUGAUUGCAAACAAUACUGAAUUAAAAUAUCCCUGCAAGUUCACUGUGACUCAAUCUAAGGUUUUAAUAAUUCAUGAAAUAAAACUAAUGUUGAUGUUAUCCAAAUCAUUCUAACGCCAACUUCUAGGUAAACAGUAAACAAGAAUAAGCAAAUUUGAGUUUUCCUAAUUAUUUGACAUUGUCAUUAGCUUGUGAUCCUUAGAUGGAAUAUAUUUUGCCAGAUCUCACCUCCCAGGGAACUGAUGAGCUUUAACUGGAAUAGUAGUGAGAAUGAUAGAGCAGGGCCCUUAACUCCUUAGAAAGGUCAAAGGAAGAGGUGAAUGUGGGCAGGGUUUCACUGGAGUAUUGACACACCAAAGAUGCUAUGUAGGUGAAAAUCUCUCCUAAUGCAUUCCCUUUCCAACGAACCUGAGCCUGGAUUCUUCAGUAACACAAUGCCUUCUGAGAAACAAUGUUGUUCCACAUUUUAGAGUUUUGGCAUGCAUAAUGGAGUUUAUGGCAGAGUUCAGAGGAUACAAUGAAACAAGAAAGGGAGGCAACUGAUGUUGUUUGAUUAUCUCCAUUAUUUUGAAGGAGCCAGGUGCUUGGGGAACCUGGUUGUACAGAAAGGUGAUGCCAAGACUCUCUUGUAUGAUUUUCCUCUCUAGCUUGGGGCUGCACCCUCUGCUGUGGGAAGGAGUCCUCAAGGUAUUAAUAUACAUCCUAUCAUUUAUUUUAGAUACAGAUAGCAUUAGAGUUUAUCAGUAAAGUUGGGCAACUCAUGGAAUAUUACGAGUAGAAAUUGUAAUUACUGUAGAAUGUAUAGUGUUUUGAAUGGCUAUUGUAUUUUUCAGCAUACAAAUUCAGAGGGGUGAAAGUAGGCAAUGACACCACUAUUUAUGUUUUUUGUUGUUGUUGUUUGUUUUUGUUUUGUUUUGUUUUGAGAUGGAGUCUUGCACUGUCACCCAGGCUGGAGGACAGUGGCAUGAUCUCUGCUCACUGCAACCUCUGCCUCCCGUGUUCAAGCGAUUCUCCUGCCUCAGCCUCCUGAGUAGCUGGGAUUACAGGCACCCGCCACCACACCUGACUAAUUUUUUGUAUUUUUAAGUAGAGACGGAGUUUUGCCAUGUUGGCCAGGCUGGUCUUGAACUCCUGAACUUGUGAUCCACCCUCCUCUGCCUUCCAAAGUGCUGGGAUUACAGGCAUGAGCCACCGCACCCAGCCCUAUUUAUGUUUUUUAAAAGCACCAUUUACCACCCAUUUGUCUAUGGACUUAAUCUAUGUCUCUAUGAGCUGGUAAACAAUAGACAGGUAAAUACAGACUUGGCUGUAUUUGAACAGCACCUUCAAAAACCAGAAGCCAGAAAUCAGGUAGCUAGAUUUGUCCAUGAAAGCAGGAGAUUCCCUUAACUGGUGAUGCCUGAAGUUGGGAUAAAGAGUCUUCCAAACAUGUGCCAUUUUGGCAUGGAUAUCUAAAGCCACCAUGAUGGCUUUAUAUUAAUGAAGGAAAUAAGUUGCAGGAUAAGUAUAUCCAUGGUCAUCCAGGGGAAGAAAAUGGCGUACAUAACUUAUAUACCAUAUUUAACCCAGAGACAGAUAUCACAGGUAAACAGUGCAAAUCACUGUCCCUAGUCUGAGCCAUAUUUAGUGUCUUGAAAGAGCCACAGUGGCUGGCUAAAAUGGCACAGUGGCAAAUCCUGACCAUGGACUGCCCUAUGCAAAAUAACUAGCUCCCCACUUUACACAGAGUACACCAUGUCAGGCCUCUGAGCCCAAGCUAAGCCAUCAUAUCCCCUGUGACCUGCACAUAUACAUCCAGAUGGCCUGAAGCAAUUGAAGAUCUACAAAAGAAGUGAAAAUUACCUUAACUGAUGACAUUCCACCAUUGUGAUGUGUUUCUGCCCCAUCCUAACUGAUCAGUGUACUUUGUAAUCUCCCCCACCCUUAAGAAGGUUCUUUGUAAUUCUUCCCACCCUUGAGAAUGUACUUUGUGAGAUCCACCCCCUGCCAGCAAAACAUUGCUCCUGACUCCACCGCCUAUCCCAAAACCUAUAAGAACUAAUGAUAAUCCCACCACCCUUUGCUGACUCUCUUUUCGGACUCAGCCCGCCUGCACCCAGGUGAAAUAAACAGCCUUGUUGCUAACCCAAA